CUGCCAGAUGCCUGUUACCUGGCUGCUUUCUCGAAAGGUUUUCAUCUUUCUUCCUCAUGAUCUAAUCUCUCUGUUCAGGGCGAGAGGCAUUCCUUCCAGAGAUCACCCCUCCUUCUUCCAUCAUCCUCCUCCCCUCCCUUUCAUUCCUAGAAGGGGAGCAUAGGGAAUACCACGCGGGAAGUCUGACGGCAGGAAACGAAUGGAAGGAAGACAGGAGAUCAGGCUCUGGUUCCCCUUAAGGACAAGAAUCAGGGUGGAGUGGUGGGGAGAACUGGGGCUUGGAGGAAGGAGAGUGCCUACUGAGGACCCUCCCAGUGCAGAAGCAUCACAGACCCAGGGAUGCAGAAAAUAGGGCCCGAGAAAGACAGUGAGGUGCAGACCUCAGUGAUGAGUCUGGGACUGACAGACGUGUCCACAGGGAAGAGGCAAUUGAGACUUGGAUUGAAGCCCUUUAAACCCCCACCCCCACCCCUGCUGAGAUUCUGCUCCCAAGGUGAUAGGAGAAAACACCAGAGAGAUGAGGUCUCAGAGUCAGAGACAUCAGUCACAGAAAGAAAGAUGGAAAGUCAGAGGGCAGUGGGGGUCUGGGGGGCUGGAGGCACCACUUACCUCAGUCACUGGCCCUGUCUUUGUGCCCCAGGUCCGAAGCCCCAGAAGGACUCUGUCUCAGACUGGGCCAUUGUGUUGAUCACUCUCACUUUGGUGGCAGCAAUUGUCAGCCUAAUGUACGGUAUCAAGAAGGCCUGCCAGUUCCGGAGGGAGAUGAGUCUGGGGUGUGGCUGUGGCUCUGUGACCCCUUACAGCAGCCACCAUGAGGGGGAGGCUGCCAGCCAGCGCUACUCUUGUCAAAUGAAAGGUAGAUUCCUGGGGUCACUGGCCCCCCCAGGUCUCUUCCACCCACAGCGUAAGGAGGAGUCUACUGUCAGUCACAAGAUUCUGCUCUCUGUCCUGCCGCCAGCCAUGCAGACUGCGGGAAGGUGCCCAGCUUCUCCGAGGGCAGUUUUCUCAUCUGUAGAAGGAAGGACCAGGGCUAAGUGGUCUGCAGGCACCUUCCAGCCCUCACGGAGCCCAGGUCUGGACAGCUGGAACCCCUGCCCCUCACCCUCUCUUCCUAGUCCCACCCUCCUCCCUGACGACCAGAGAAGCUCUUUAGCUGAGGACAGUCUGCUCACGGCUUCCCUUCUCACUUCCCUCCACAGGGAGCCCCCUCAGGCUGGCUCUUGAGCCCCCAAGGCCCUCUGAUUCUCUCCCCUCAGGGCAGGUGCAGGACCCUCCUCUGUGGUGCCCCCUCGGUCUGCUAUGGGAGGGUGGUGAACAAGUUAUUGCUAAAUAAAAUGGCACUUCCUCCACUUGUCUCCCAGAUGCUGUGGGUUUGCCCAAGUGCAUGGGCUUUUGUGUCAUGUGGGCCCGGAAGGGCCAAGUCUGGUCUCUGCCAGUUACCAGGGCAAGUCAUUCCCUGAUCCGA